GCAUGUGUCUGCUGCUCCCUAGUCUGGGCCAUGAGUGAGGGUGGAGGCCAAGUCUCAUGCAUUUUUGCAGCCCCCACAAGACUGUGCAGGUGGCCGGCCCUCAUUGAAUGCGGGGUUAAUUUAACUCAGCCUCUGUGUGAGUGGAUGAUUCAGGUUGCCAGAGACAGAACCCUCAGCUUAGCAUGGGAAGUAGCUUCCCUGUUGACCCUGAGUUCAUCUGAGGUUGGCUUGGAAGGUGUGGGCACCAUUUGGCCCAGUUCUUACAGCUCUGAAGAGAGCAGCAGGAAUGGGGCUGAGCAGGGAAGACAACUUUCCAUUGAAGGCCCCUUUCAGGGCCAGAACUGUCCCUCCCACCCUGCAGCUGCCCUGCCUCUGCCCAUGAGGGGUGAGAGUCAGGCGACCUCAUGCCAAGUGUAGAAAGGGGCAGAUGGGAGCCCCAGGUUAU